ACUUGCUGGGGUCGGGGCUGCGCGACGGCGCAGGGGCUGCGGGGAGCGCCGCGCAGGCCGUGCAGUUCCUAGCGAGGAGGCGCCGCCGCCAUUGCCGCUCUCUCGGUGAGCGCAGCCCCGCUCUCCGGGCCGGGCCUUCGCGGGCCACCGGCGCCAUGGGCCAGUGCGGCAUCACCUCCUCCAAGACCGUGCUGGUCUUUCUCAACCUCAUCUUCUGGGGGGCAGCUGGCAUUUUAUGCUAUGUGGGAGCCUAUGUCUUCAUCACUUAUGAUGACUAUGACCACUUCUUUGAAGAUGUGUACACGCUCAUCCCUGCUGUAGUGAUCAUAGCUGUAGGAGCCCUGCUUUUCAUCAUUGGGCUAAUUGGCUGCUGUGCCACAAUCCGGGAAAGUCGCUGUGGACUUGCCACGUUUGUCAUCAUCCUGCUCUUGGUUUUUGUCACAGAAGUUGUUGUAGUGGUUUUGGGAUAUGUUUACAGAGCAAAGGUGGAAAAUGAGGUUGAUCGCAGCAUUCAGAAAGUGUAUAAGACCUACAAUGGAACCAACCCUGAUGCUGCUAGCCGGGCUAUUGAUUAUGUACAGAGACAGCUGCAUUGUUGUGGAAUUCACAACUACUCAGACUGGGAAAAUACAGAUUGGUUCAAAGAAACCAAAAACCAGAGUGUCCCUCUUAGCUGCUGCAGAGAGACUGCCAGCAAUUGUAAUGGCAGCCUGGCCCACCCUUCCGACCUCUAUGCUGAGGGGUGUGAGGCUCUAGUAGUGAAGAAGCUACAAGAAAUCAUGAUGCAUGUGAUCUGGGCCGCACUGGCAUUUGCAGCUAUUCAGCUGCUGGGCAUGCUGUGUGCUUGCAUCGUGUUGUGCAGAAGGAGUAGAGAUCCUGCUUACGAGCUCCUCAUCACUGGCGGAACCUAUGCAUAGUUGACAACUCAAGCCUGAGCUUUUUGGUCUUGUUCUGAUUUGGAAGGUGAAUUGAGCAGGUCUGCUGCUGUUGGCCUCUGGAGUUCAUUUAGUUAAAGCACAUGUACACUGGUGUUGGACAGAGCAGCUUGGCUUUUCAUGUGCCCACCUACUUACCUACUACCUGCGACUUUCUUUUUCCUUGUUCUAGCUGACUCUUCAUGCCCCUAAGAUUUUAAGUACGAUGGUGAACGUUCUAAUUUCAGAACCAAUUGCGAGUCAUGUAGUGUGGUAGAAUUAAAGGAGGACACGAGCCUGCUUCUGUUACCUCCAAGUGGUAACAGGACUGAUGCCGAAAUGUCACCAGGUCCUUUCAGUCUUCACAGUGGAGAACUCUUGGCCAAAGGUUUUUGCGGGGAGGAGGAGGAAACCAGCUUUCUGGUUAAGGUUAACACCAGAUGGUGCCCCUCAUUGGUGUCCUUUUAAAAAAUAUUUACUGUAGUCCAAUAAGAUAGCAGCUGUACAAAAUGACUAAAAUAGAUUGUAGGAUCAUAUGGCGUAUAUCUUGGUUCAUCUUCAAAAUCAGAGACUGAGCUUUGAAACUAGUGGUUUUUAAUCAAAGUUGGCUUUAUAGGAGGAGUAUAAUGUAUGCACUACUGUUUUAAAAGAAUUAGUGUGAGUGUGUUUUUGUAUGAAUGAGCCCAUUCAUGGUAAGUCUUAAGCUUGUUGGAAAUAAUGUACCCAUGUAGACUAGCAAAAUAGUAUGUAGAUGUGAUCUCAGUUGUAAAUAGAAAAAUCUAAUUCAAUAAACUCUGUAUCAGCCCCCAACAUAUUAUUUUUCAUUAUUUGGGGGAUAUUUCAGUUCCAGAGCAGCAGUAUCAUGUUUUCUUUGUUGGUGCUGUCUAUAGUUCAUCAUGGUUUACGUGUGUUUUCGUUAUAGCUGUUGCCAGAUUCUAAAGGGCUUGAUAUUCAAAAAACCACAGAUGCUUUCAGUCCAGUAUAUCCUAGAAAUAUAGAGCUCUACUUUGUGCAAUGCACUGGGGAUACAGUGGCGAUACUGUCCUUGUCUUCAAGGAGUUCGGAGUCCUAGUAUAGGAGACAUACAUAGGAGAAGAUAAUUUUCACACUGCAGUGGUUGUAGUAAUAGAAUGGGAGUCCAAAGGGGAGUUCCGGAGAGGUCAGGGGUGACUUCCUGGAGGAGAUGCCCAAGCUUGGAGGCUGGAUAGGCUUUGUUGAAAGAUGGUACACAAGAGUGUGAAACAAAAUUGUGUGUGCAGGGAGCUUAAAAUACAAGGCUGGGGAAAGAAGUUGGAGAAGCAGGAAAGCCCAGGCCCUCUAGUGUCUUACGGAACAUCCUGUGGAGGUGAGAGCUGACUUGUAGGUGGAAGCAGCUCUUUGGAGGUUUGAUUUGGAAGGUGAACUGAGAAGAAGGUGGUGAUGCAAGCCGGCCGUGCUGAAGCCAGGAUGAAUUGGUGUGACUGGGCUUCAGUUAGGCUGGCAUAGCAGUUGAGAGAGCUUAGCAGUGGGCAGCAGGGCACUGUUGGGGGCGGUGGUGAGCGGUGGAUUCUGGCUGUUUGGAGGCAGGACAGUGGUGGAAUUCGAUCAUUGAUUGGACGUGGGACAGAGAAGGGAGAAGAGAAGACUCAUCUAGGAUGAGUCCCAGGUUUCUGGCUCAGUCAACUGGGGAAACAAAGUCACAGAGCUAGGGAGUAGUUAGAGAACACAUCUGGGGGUGUGACUCAUGGUCAGUUUUGGGCUCGUCAGUUUUGAGAUGCCCAAAUAUCAUGCAGAUCUGUCCCACCUGAAAAUGGAGAAGACACGGGAAAGGAGAGGAGUAAAAACUAACUCCUUUUCACAAAGUGGAAGUUACCAGAAUGUGAUUUCAGAGGCCCCGGGGGAUUUAUCAUGUGACUACUGACCCAUCCCACCUCUUGCCCCUGCCUGUUGCACAGUGGGCAAGAAUGUUUGUGACCUUUCACUACCACCACCUCCCCCGAGCAUGGUCCCCCCAGUUUUCAAUAUGAACCAUCCUGUGGGUACCCUGUCACAGGCUGGCCCUGAGGUGAGCAAUAUUUGGACUGUGAUGUUGGUUGUUCUCCACUCUUUCUACAGGACAGAACAGGGCCUCUAGAGUGGGAAAUGGCUUUGGGAAAUAUGCCAAGCAGUAGCCUUGUUCUUCAACUUGCCCAAGAGGAUAAUUCUCCACACCCUUCCUGUACUCAGUCCUCAGUUUGCCUGGUGAGAGAGCAGCCUCCUCCCGUGUGCUCUGCCAGCUGGACCCAGACUGGCCAUAUUACCAGUGAGACCAAAAAGAUGGAGGUGGGGAGGUAGCUCUGAGGUCUGGGAAACCAUUCCAGCUCCUGCCAGUUUUAACUUGUGUUUAAUUCCUGGCACAGUUGUCCUGGAAAUGCCUUUUUCUCUUGCCUGGGAACCACUAGAAGGGGAUGUUGUCUGUGUUGGCCAGGGCCAUGCAAAUUCAACAUCUUGUUUCUGCCCUUCCCCCGUGUAGCUGAGGCUAGGUGUUGGCAUUACCCAGUGCUUGUUCUUCAGAGAGCAAAAGCACUGCUCGUCAUGUCUGAAAUUUAGUGAGUGAGCUCACCCACUAGGCUGGUGUUUCCUGCCCGUGGCUGCACAUUGGAAGCACCGGGGCACUUUGAGAACUACAGAUGCCUGGGUCCCAGAGCAUCUAAGGUGCUCUAGGGUGUGUCCAGGACACAGCCCUGGUUGAGGACCACUGCUAUAUUGUAUGGCCUCUUUUAAAAAAGUUAAUUUUACUUGGAAAUGAUUUCAAAGCUACAGAAAAGUUGCAAGAAUAAAAACUGUACAAAUGAGGCUCAAAUAUCCUUUGCCCAGAUACACCUAUUAACAUUUCGUCCCAUUCUAUCUGUCAUGUGUGUUCUCAAAUGUGUGUGCGUUCUCUCUCCCUUGCGCCAACCCCCUGUCUCUCCCUCUCCCUCCCUCCUGCUGCCUCCACACCUGUCAUGGCCUUUUACCCCUAAUACCUCAGUGGGUACUUACCAAGAAGAAGAUACUCUCUGACGACUGCAGUACAGUUGUCAAAUUCCGUCCAUCUAACACUGAUAGAAUACCUCACCACUCAUAUUCCCAUUGGCCGCAUCGUGUCCUCUAUAGCACCUUUCCCUCUGCGGUGCUGGAUCUGGUCUGGAUCAGGUAAUCAGUUGAGUUGUCAUGUCUCCUUGGUCUUCUUUAAUCUGGAUCAUUUCCAUAGCUUUGUCUGUGAUGAUAGGAACAGUUUGUAAGGAUACAGUUCGUUUUAGGUGGUGCUGCUUAUCUGUGUUUGUCUGCGAUUUCCUCGUGAUUAGAUUUGGUUUUGCAUUCCAGGUGGCUGAACCACUACCUGCGUCACGCGGCCUCUCAGGGCAUCGCAUCUCGAGGCACACAAUGCCCAUCUGCCCCACAGUGGGGAUGUUCGUUUUGAUCAUCUAGUCCAAGGAGGAGGAAAUGUGAACAGGAAGGUUUUAAUAUAAGUAAUUGUUAACUGUGUAGAAGGUAGUUAACUACUAAAAGGGAUAAAAAAGAGCUCUAAAGCAGCUUAGCAGAGAACAGCCAUCACCCCUAGGGCUAAGGGAAGAGAAAACAGAGAAGGAACGUGGAAACUCAGAGGAGGUUCCCCAAGGUGGAGAGACCUCCGAGGGGUGGCUGUGGUUGCCUGGGAUAUGCUGCCUGUCCCAUGCUGGAGAAUCAACUUACUGGAGGUGCCCCCCCGCCAAGCCACAGGAGCAGAGAGCUGUCACGGUGGGGAAUGCUGCUGGGACCCGUGCAGGACGAAAGGAGACAGAAGAAAAAGGCCAUCUUCCUCCUCUAGCCUUGUUAGCCCCUUCAGAGCCCACUGUGGGUCAGGCUGGCAAAGGGUAAAGGAGUUUUCAGAGCCCCCUCUUCAGUGUGACAAGGAAGGGCAAGGUCAGGGAAAUUUGGAGUUAAGAGGCAAUAAAUGAGUACCUGGCACACCUAGUCGAGGUGUGUCCACUUUCUCCAUAGCAUGGUUACUGUUUUUUUCUUUUCAACUAAUAAGAAAUCUCUGGAGACACACUGUCUCCAUGUACAUACCCUGUUCCUCAUGAGACUCUUCCCCAUUCCCCGACCAGGUUCAGCAAAUGUUGCUGAUUCUGGCCUGAUUCAAUCUUUAUGAUGACUGCCAAGCGACGUUUCUGCAGCCCAGCACUCCUUCCUCAUUUGCCAGUCAUCCCUCCCUUCUCCUUCAUUUAUUUUCAUAUAUCCACUAUGGAUUCCCAUUUUUUCAAAAGUCGACUUCAUCAUUGACCUUUGGGGAUGGGGGAAGAGUUCCUCAGAUAGUUCCCGACUUGGCCAGCGAGAGCCCCUUCGAGUGCCUCCUAUAUCCCAGCAUUUUUGGAAGCACUCCCCUAAUUUCUGAUCUAACAAGAUGUUCCAGGCCCCUGGGCACCAGCCAUGGAUCAGUGUUUGUCCCAGGAGCCCUGGUCCCUGGCACUAGGUGUGCUUAUUGCAGCUGGGGUGUCUUUGCUUCUUGUCCUAUAGAUGAUUGACAGAGCUUGUCUUACUGCCUUUUUUAAGUGUAUUUUUUUAAACAAAAGUAAUUGGUGCUUUAAAAAAUGUGAACAAUACAGACAUCUGUAAAGAAGUACCCACAGGGAAGCAAGUUCAGCAGUUCAGCAAUGGCAUGUGUCUUUGCAGACUACAUACACAGAAACAGACUUGGUAUUGGGUUUUGGUUUUUGCUUUUUGCUAAUAGGAAUUUUAUCCUACAAGAUCCUCUUUCUGUCUUCACAACAUAGUCUGAUGCUCCUUCCAUGUCUAACUGUAGGAUUUGUCAUUCCAUUGUGUUAGCUGUGUGGGUACAUUAGUACCAUGAUUAACCAAGGUGUAUAAAGGGCAGGCCUGCAGGCUGCCUCCAGUGCCUCCACUACUCGCCACAGUGAUCAUCUCUAUACACACACUGCAGUCAUUUACAAUUUUUAAAAUGAAAACAAUUUUUAUUGAGAUGCAAUUCACAUGGCAUAAAAUUAACGAUUUUAAAGUAAAGAAGUUGCCUUGAGUACAUUCACCAUGCUAUAGAACCACUGCCUGUAUCUAGUUUCAAAGCACUUUCAUCACCCUGUGUCAUGUAUUUUUACAUGAACUCCAAGGGUGGAUUCUUGUUAGUUGGAUUUACUCUGGAUGGAAAAGUCAUGUUUGGCUGGGUGCAGUGGCUCAUGCCUGUAAUCAUAGCACUUUGGGAGGUCGAGACAGGUGGGUCACUUGAGAUCAGGAGUUCAAAACCAGCCUGGCCAACAUGGUGAAACCCAUCUCUAUUAAAAAUACAAAAAAUUAGCAGGGCCUGGUGGCAUGCACCUGUAAUCCCAGCUACUUGGGAGGCUGAGGCAGGAGAAUCGCUUGAACCGGGAGGCAGAGGUUGCAGUGAGCCGAGAUUAUGCCACUGCACUCCAGCCUGGGUGACAGAGCAAGACUCUGUCUC